GUAGUUCCGGUGGCGACUGCGGCGCAUGGCGGCCCUGGGACAUCUUGCUGGGGAGGCAGCGGCGGCCCCAGGCCCGGGUACUCCCUGCGCGUCCCGCGGAGCCCGGCUUCCCGGCCCAGUUUCCAGCGCCCGGAAUCCUUCCACUGUCUGUCUCUGCCCAGAGCAACCUACGUGCAGUAACGCUGACUCCAGAGCGCACCCGUUGGGCGAUGAAGGCGGCACAGCGUCGAAAAAACAAAAGAAUAAGAAGAAAACGCGGAACAGGGCCUCUGUGGCAAAUGGAGGCGAGAAGGCCUCAGAGAAACUCGCCCCAGAAGAAGUUCCCCUAAGCGCUGAGGCCCAGGCACAACAGUUGGCCCAGGAAUUGGCUUGGUGUGUGGAGCAACUGGAGCUGGGCCUCAAGAGGCAGAAACCCACCCCGAAACAGAAAGAGCAGGCUAUUGGAGCAAUCCGAACCCUGCGCAGCAAAAGAACGCCCUUGCCCCGGAAGAGGCAGCUGAUGCACUCCUUGUUUGGAGACUAUAGGGCUCAGAUGGAAGCCGAAUGGCGUGAGGCCCUGCGGGCUCUCAGAGCUGCUGCUUAUUCAGCCCAGGUGCAACCUGUAGAUGGAGCCACCAGAAAGAAGAGCCAAAGGGUCUGCAGGCCUCGCUCUAUAUGGAGAGCCAAAGCCACUCUGGACAUGCCUGAUGAAGAGUUUAGGUUCAAUUUCUUUUAGCGUCUCCCCGAACCUGAAACAAUCCCCCUCCCUUGGGGUGGUGUAGGGGUUUGUUUUGAGUGCAGAGCCUUUCCAGGACUUCUGUUGUCAGAGAACCCUGGAGUUGGUCUGUCCCUGGCUGGUCCAAGGAUUUGUAGCUGUUGUGAAGGUGUGAGACCAUCAGAUAGGCAAAAGACCCCGUUCGUUUUCUGAUGAAAUGUUCUCUCUUUCAGAAGAGAGAGAGAGGUGCAUUUAGAAAAUAUGCAAUAAAUUGAAGUGAGUGUUCAAAGUAUUGUAGAAGGAAUAUUGUACUCAGUCUUUAGGAUUAGAUUAAGUGGCUGUUGGUAACAAAGAUUAGUGGAGAAGCUGUAUAAUCGUACACUGGUUUUCACUUUUGAAAGGAAUCCCUGUCAAAUGGUUUAGUGCUUAAUGCUGUUAUGUCAUAUUGCCCUAAUCUCUAUUUUUGAUAAAAUUGGAUAAGGAGUGAAAGAGUAUGCUGACCACCUAUGUUAGAGGAAGUACAGAAGAUGCAGGGGUGUGGUAUCCCUGGGUCCAGUCCCUCACCUGGUACCUUUGUGCAUGUUGCCUUCAUUCCUGAGCAGGUAUCAUCCUCAGGGAACCAGCAUGGCACCUACCAGGCCAGGCUCUGUUCUUAGGAGCAAGGAGCUUCUUGCGCUAACAGUUCUGGCCUGAGACCUGGAUUGAGCCUUGGCAGACUUCUUGUCUAAAUGUUGGCCAUUCAGUCUCAGGCCCUCUGUUCCAUGGAAUUGGGAAUCUCCAGGUGACCUAAUCCUCAUUGGUGGCUUGAUGUUUGCUGGUAUCUUCCAAACUCAGUUCCCAGACUAGAUUGAUACCUGGAGCCCAGCUGCCUACUCAGCAUUUCCACUUGGGUGCUUCAUAGGCAUUUCAAACCUGAUGUGUUUAAAACACUUGAUUAGGCUCCGGUUUUCCUUUGGCUUCUGCUUUUCAGUGAAUGGCAUGACUGCCUAUGUGGGUGGCAAGCCACCCAGGUGCCGAGGAAAGAGACUGAGGGCACGAGCUGUUCCAGUAUAAUAAAAUAUAUAAAAUAAGAAGAGUUAUACUAGAUCUAGAUCAUAGACAUGAUUAUAUGUGAGUAUCAUUAAUCAUUAGUUUAUAGCAAUUACUCUUUAUUCCAAUAUUAUAAUAAUCCUCACUCUACAAUCAUAACCUAGGAAAAACCAGGCCAUACAGAGAUAGGAGCCGAGGGGACAUAGUGCGAAGUGGCCAGAAGACAAGAGUGUGAGCCUUCUCUUAUGCCCGGACAGGGCCACCAGAGGGCUUGGUCUAGCAGUAACACCAGUGUCUGGGAAGAUGCCUGUUGCAAAGUGGACCAUGGUCUAGCAGUAGCAUCAGUGUCAAGGAAAAACACCCACUACUUAGCAGACUGGGAAAAGGAGCCUCCCUUUCCCCGGGGGAGUUUAGAGAAGACUACUCCUCCACCUCUUGUGGAGGGCCUGACAUCAGUCAGGCCCGCCCGCAGUUAUCCAGAGGCCUGUCUCCCUGUGAUGCUGUGCUUCAGUGGUCACGCUCCUAGUCCGCUUUCAUGUUCCAUCCUGUAUACCUGGCUCUGCCUUUUAGAUAGCAGGAGCAAAUUAGUGAAAGUACUAAAUGUCUGAUAUGCAGAAAUAAUGGCAUAAGCUGUCUCUCUCUCUUCUCUCUCUCUCUGCCUCUGCUGCCAGGCAGGGAAGGGCCCCCUGUCCAGUGGACACAUGACCCAUGUGACCUUACCUAUUAUUGGAGAUGGUUCACAUUCCUUACCCUGCCCCUUUGUCUUAUAUCCAAUAAAUAUCAGUGCAGCCUGGCAUUUGGGGCCACUACUGGUCUCCGCGUCUUGGUGGUAGUGGUCCCCCAGGCCCAGGUGUCUUUUCUUUUA